GAGGGGCCCUCGGGAGACGCGGCUGCCGGCACGCGGGCGCCCAGGGCACAGGUCCCGCCGGGCCGCCUUGGGCGUUGCUGGCUGAGGCCCAGGGCAGCAGGUGCCAACGGUCAGGAAAGGCAGGGAGCCGAAGGCUGCCGGUGGGCGCUUCGCGUUUUGUUCCAAGGCGAAGGUGUGUGGAUUCUCCGCAGCCCGUCGGUCAGCUACUCAGGAGGCUGAGGCAGGAGAAUCAUUUGAACCCAGGAGCUGGAGGUUGCAGUAUUUCAUGCCUACGCAGGUACUGGCACACGGAUGAGGAGUCGUAGAAGAGGGGCCUGCAGAUUGUGCUCUCAGCAAGCCUGUCGUCUAGUGGAAGACACUGGCCGGGACACAGAGCCCACGUGUGGACACCGCUGUGGGUUGGUGGCAGGGGUCGAGCAGGUGCCAUCAGGCACAUGAACGGUGGAGUCUUCAAAGGUGUGAGCAGCUGCUGGAAGAGGAGGUGCUCCUGAAGACACUGCGGCCGGCCCGCCUGUGCCCUUGGUGCCCUGGCUGCCUAGAGAGCCUCACCCCUGGGCCCUGGGGCCAGGACUCCAGGACUCUGACUACCUGCCCUCCCCCAGCCUCAGCGGCUGCACCUCCUCGUUAGUACUGAUGCACUGACCUCGGCACACAGCUGGGAGGGGUUGGGGGCUGGGUCAUGGCUGCUCCCAGGCCCCACCCAGGCUCCUGAGCCUAGAAGGUGAAAAGAGGACUCUCAGGGGCUCACAGGGGCUCUCACUGCUGGUUGGCCCUGCCCUCCCUUCCCCCUCAGCAGGGUGCCCGGAAGCUGGAACCUUGUUAUCUGGGUAAUUAGUUUCAGACCCUGCACUGAGGCCGGCCAGGUCUCGGGGCUGCCUCCCAUAGGUUGUGCACCCUGACCCCGAGAGGGAGGCGAGGCGCUGCUUGUCGACAGCUAGAGGCUGGCCUGGGGAGCAGGUUUGGGGUGCCCUCCCACACUGCCCUCCCUGCCCCGGCCCAUGCCCCCCAGGGCUGCCUGGGCCUGGUUAUUGUGUGGGGCCUCCUGACCCAGCCAAGGGCACGAAGCUCUGGGAAGGGGAUGCCCCCGAGGGUGCCAGUCCAGCUAGCUGCCCCACCCCUCAGGCCCAGCCUGGCCCCCAAGCUCCCCACUCUGGUGCCCCGAGCAGCCCUGUGGGCAAGCAGCCGCCGCCAUGGCCGAGCACCUGGAGCUGCUGGCAGAGAUGCCCAUGGUGGGCAGGAUGAGCACACAGGAGCGGCUGAAGCAUGCCCAGAAGCGGCGCGCCCAGCAGGUGAAGAUGUGGGCCCAGGCUGAGAAGGAGGCCCAGGGCAAGAAGGGUCCUGGGGAGCGUCCCCGGAAGGAGGCAGCCAGCCAAGGGCUCCUGAAGCAGGUCCUCUUCCCUCCCAGUGUUGUCCUUCUGGAGGCCGCUGCCCGAAAUGACCUGGAAGAAGCCCCAGCUGUGUGGGUUCCACUUCUGGUGCUCUGGAGUCUUGGGGGAAGAGGCACUGUGGUGGCCCUUGAGACUCCUUCCUGCCUCCCUCCGGAGCAGAGAGUAAAGAGGAGCCGGCAGUGUCUGGCCUGCAUCUUUCCAUGUGGACAGGAGCCCUCCCGGGAGGCCUGGAGGCAGAGGGAAGAGGCGGAGGGUGCCAUGGUCCACAGGGAGCUGUGGGAAGUCCGCCAGUUCCUUGGGAGUGGGGUCAGCCCUGACUUGGCCAACGAGGACGGCCUGACGGCCCUGCACCAGUGCUGCAUUGAUGAUUUCCGAGAGAUGGUGCAGCAGCUCCUGGAGGCUGGGGCCAACAUCAAUGCCUGUGACAGUGAGUGCUGGACGCCUCUGCAUGCUGCGGCCACCUGCGGCCACCUGCACCUGGUGGAGCUGCUCAUCGCCAGUGGCGCCAAUCUCCUGGCGGUCAACACCGACGGGAACAUGCCCUAUGACCUGUGUGAUGAUGAGCAGACGCUGGACUGCCUGGAGACUGCCAUGGCCGACCGUGGCAUCACCCAGGACAGCAUCGAGGCCGCCCGGGCCGUGCCAGAACUGCGCAUGCUGGACGACAUCCGGAGCCGGCUGCAGGCCGGGGCAGACCUCCAUGCCCCCCUGGACCACGGGGCCACGCUGCUGCACGUCGCAGCCGCCAACGGGUUCAGCGAGGCGGCUGCCCUGCUGCUGGAACACCGAGCCAGCCUGAGCGCUAAGGACCAAGACGGCUGGGAGCCGCUGCACGCCGCGGCCUACUGGGGCCAGGUGCCCCUGGUGGAGCUGCUCGUGGCGCACGGGGCCGACCUGAACGCAAAGUCCCUGAUGGACGAGACGCCCCUUGAUGUGUGCGGGGACGAGGAGGUGCGGGCCAAGCUGCUGGAGCUGAAGCACAAGCACGACGCCCUCCUGCGCGCCCAGAGCCGCCAGCGCUCCUUGCUGCGCCGCCGCACCUCCAGCGCCGGCAGCCGCGGGAAGGUGGUGAGGCGGGUGAGCCUAACCCAGCGCACCGACCUGUACCGCAAGCAGCACGCCCAGGAGGCCAUCGUGUGGCAACAGCCGCCGCCCACCAGCCCGGAGCCGCCCGAGGACAACGAUGACCGCCAGACAGGCGCAGAGCUCAGGCCGCCGCCCCCGGAGGAGGACAACCCCGAAGUGGUCAGGCCGCACAAUGGCCGAGUAGGGGGCUCCCCAGUGCGGCAUCUAUACUCCAAGCGACUAGACCGGAGUGUCUCCUACCAGCUGAGCCCCCUGGACAGCACCACCCCCCACACCCUGGUCCACGACAAGGCCCACCACACCCUGGCUGACCUGAAGCGCCAGCGAGCUGCUGCCAAGCUGCAGCGACCCCCACCUGAGGGGCCCGAGAGCCCUGAGACAGCUGAGCCUGGCCUGCCUGGUGACACGGUGACCCCCCAGCCUGACUGUGGCUUCAGGGCAGGCGGGGACCCACCCCUGCUCAAGCUCACAGCCCCGGCGGUGGAGGCUCCCGUGGAGAGGAGGCCGUGCUGCCUGCUCAUGUGAGGCUGUUGCUCAGCAUGCAGGGGCCCUGUCGCGGGCACAGCCCAAGGCUGCCUCCCCACGGUGCGUGCCCUGGUGCUGCGGGUGCAGCACGGAAACCCCGGCUUCUACUGUACAGGACACUGGCCCCUCUCAGGUCAGAAGACAUGCCUGGAGGGAUGUCUGGCUGCAAAGACUAUUUUUAUCCUGCAACUCUUGAUAAAGGGCUGUUUUGCCAUGGA